GAGCCUGCGAGUCCGCGAGCCAGCGAGCUGCGGCUGCGGCCUCCCCUGCGCGCAGCUACCCGGGCGUCCCGGCCCGCGGCCCCGCUAACCCCGGGGCCCGCGCCCCCGCGGCAGGGAUGCAUCAUGGCCACGCUGGCUUGCCGGGUGCAGUUCUUGGACGACACGGACCCUUUCAACAGCACCAACUUCCCCGAGCCCAGCCGGCCGCCGCUGUUCACGUUCCGCGAGGACCUCGCGCUCGGCACCCAGCUGGCGGGGGUCCAUAGGCUGCUGCAGGCGCCGCACAAGCUGGAUGACUGUACUCUGCAGCUCUCUCACAAUGGCGCCUACCUGGAUUUGGAGGCCACCCUGGCAGAGCAGCGGGAUGAGUUGGAAGGCUUCCAGGAUGACGCCGGGCGGGGCAAGAAGCACAGCAUCAUCCUAAGGACGCAGCUGUCUGUGAGGGUCCAUGCCUGCAUCGAAAAACUAUACAACUCCAGCGGACGAGAUUUGAGAAGGGCCCUCUUCUCCCUGAAGCAGAUAUUUCAGGAUGACAAGGAUUUGGUGCAUGAAUUUGUAGUGGCUGAAGGUCUGACAUGUUUGAUCAAGGUGGGAGCUGAGGCUGAUCAGAACUAUCAGAACUACAUCUUAAGGGCUUUGGGCCAGAUUAUGUUGUAUGUGGAUGGAAUGAAUGGAGUAAUAAACCGCAAUGAAACCAUUCAGUGGCUGUACACUCUCAUUGGGUCAAAGUUCCGCCUGGUGGUGAAGACAGCCCUGAAGCUGCUGCUCGUCUUUGUAGAGUACUCGGAGUCCAACGCACCUCUCCUAAUUCAGGCUGUCACUGCUGUUGACACGAAAAGAGGGGUCAAACCUUGGUCAAAUAUCAUGGAAAUCCUGGAGGAAAAAGAUGGAGUUGAUACGGAGCUACUGGUUUAUGCAAUGACUUUGGUGAACAAGACGUUAUCAGGACUACCAGACCAAGACACCUUCUACGACGUCGUGGACUGCCUGGAGGAGCUGGGCAUUGCUGCUGUGUCCCAGAGGCACUUGAACAAGAAAGGGACUGACCUGGACUUAGUGGAGCAACUCAACAUUUAUGAGGUGGCGCUCAGGCACGAGGAUGGCGAUGAGACCACGGAGCCACCCCCCAGUGGGUGCCGGGACCGGAGGAGGGCCAGCGUGUGUUCCAGUGGCGGAGGCGAGCACCGGGGCCUGGACCGCAGAAGGAGCCGCAGGCACUCGGUGCAGAGCAUCAAGAGCACCCUGUCGGCCCCCACCAGUCCCUGCUCCCAGUCAGCUCCCAGCUUCAAGCCCAACCAAGUGCGAGAUCUGCGUGAAAAGGAGGAGGAGGAGGAAGAGGAGCAGCCAAUCACGGAGCCCAGUUCCGAAGAAGAGAGAGAGGAUGAUGCUUCCUGUCAGGGCAAGGACAGCAAGGUCGGCGCUGCCUCAGGGCAGAGCCCCACUGGAAGGGAUGCUGCUCCCAAGAGCUCUGCCCUCCCUGCUGUCUCGAAUGCCAGCUCGCAGGGAAAGCCGCUUCUGGUUGGCACUGCAGGCGGGACCACCUGGCACAGUGGGUCCUCUGGGUCUGAGGCCACCCCAUCUGCCCUCCUGUCACCCCCUGCCUCAGCUGCUCGGCCCUCCUCCGCCACACCAGGCUCCCUGAAGGUGUCACCGACCAUAGACAAGCUGCCCUACGUGCCCCACAGCCCCUUCCACCUCUUCUCCUAUGACUUUGAGGACUCCUCCCUGUCCACCAAGGAGAAGGAAGCAGAGUCCCAGAAGGAAAACAGUUCCUCUGAUUCUUUCUCUUUGAGCACAUAUUCUGCCUCUGAGCCUUACCACUUCCGAUCUUUCUCUUCUAAUAGAUACAGCAAUUUUGGCAAUAACUCUUAUCACUCCUCAAGACCCUCAUCUGGAUCCAGUGUGCCCACCACCCCCACAUCAUCCGUCUCACCCCCACAGGAGGCCAGGUUGGAAAGACAAAAAUCUGAAACAAGAAGACCCGAGGCAUUCAGUGAUUUUCCCCAAGCAUUGCCUAGGUCAUCACCGAGUGGUCUUCUCACAUCAUCCUUCAGGCAGCACCAAGAGUCACUGGCAGCAGAGAGAGAGAGGCGGCGGCAGGAGAGAGAAGAAAGGUUGCAGAGAAUAGAGCGGGAAGAAAGAAACAAAUUCAGCCGAGAUUAUUUAGACAAAAGAGAGGAGCAAAGGCAAGCAAGAGAAGAAAGAUACAAAUACUUGGAACAGUUGGCAGCUGAGGAGCACGAGAAGGAGCUGAGAAGCCGGAGUGUGAGCCGGGGCAGAGCCGACCUCUCCUUGGACCUGACCUCGCCAGCAGCCCCAGCCUGCCUGGCUCCUCUGAGCCAUAGCCCCUCAUCUUCAGACUCUCAAGAGGCUCUCACGGUGUCUGCCUCCUCCCCAGGAACCCCUCACCAUCCCCAAGCAAGUGCCGGGGAUCCUGAACCCGAAUCAGAGGCAGAACCGGAAGCAGAGGCAGGGGCGGGGCAGGUUGCUGAUGAAGCUGGCCAGGACAUAGCCUCUGCCCACGAGGGUGCAGAGACUGAAGUGGAGCAGGCACUAGAGCAAGAGCCGGAAGAAAGAGCCUCCCUCAGUGAAAAAGAGAGGCAGAACGAGGGGGUGAACGAGAGGGACAACUGCUCUGCCUCCAGCGUCUCGUCCUCCAGCAGCACGUUGGAGAGGGAGGAGAAGGAGGACAAGCUCUCCAGGGACAGGACAACUGGUUUGUGGCCCGCAGGUGUCCAGGAUGCAGGUGUAAAUGGACAGUGUGGCGACAUCCUCACCAACAAACGGUUCAUGCUUGACAUGCUGUAUGCCCAUAACAGGAAGUCUCCGGAUGAUGAGGAGAAGGGGGAUGGGGAGGCUGGGAGGACCCAGCAGGAGGCAGAGGCGGUAGCCAGCCUUGCUACCAGGAUAUCCACCCUGCAGGCCAACUCUCAGACCCAGGAUGAGAGUGUCAGGAGGGUGGAUGUCGGCUGUUUGGACAAUCGGGGCAGUGUGAAAGCAUUUGCUGAGAAAUUCAACAGUGGGGACCUGGGGAGAGGUUCCAUCUCCCCUGAUGCUGAGCCCAAUGACAAGGUCCCAGAAACAGCGCCGGUGCAGCCGAAGACAGAGUCUGAUUACAUCUGGGACCAGCUCAUGGCCAAUCCAAGAGAGCUCAGAAUCCAAGACAUGGAUUUCACUGACCUGGGGGAGGAGGAUGACAUUGAUGUCCUAGAUGUGGACCUGGGUCACAGGGAGGCCCCUGGGCCACCUCCCCCACCCCCACCCACCUUUCUGGGUUUGCCGCCCCCACCCCCUCCGCCCCUGUUGGACAGCAUUCCUCCCCCUCCUGUCCCUGGUAAUUUAUUGGUUCCUCCUCCUCCAGUGUUCAACGCUCCUCAGGGCUUAGGGUGGUCCCAGGUACCCAGGGGUCAGCCCACAUUCACUAAGAAAAAGAAGACCAUCCGUUUGUUCUGGAAUGAAGUUCGGCCUUUUGACUGGCCAUGUAAAAACAACCGACGCUGCAGAGAAUUCCUGUGGUCAAAACUGGAACCCAUUAAGGUGGACACUUCCAGACUGGAGCACCUGUUUGAGUCUAAAUCCAAGGAACUGUCUGUCUCAAAGAAAACUGCUGCAGAUGGAAAAAGGCAAGAGAUCAUUGUUCUGGAUUCCAAGAGGAGUAACGCCAUCAAUAUUGGUCUGACGGUGCUGCCCCCUCCAAGGACGAUUAAGAUCGCCAUUUUGAAUUUUGAUGAGUAUGCCUUAAACAAAGAAGGAAUCGAGAAAAUUCUAACGAUGAUUCCCACCGAUGAGGAGAAGCAGAAAAUCCAGGAAGCUCAGCUGGCCAACCCUGAAAUCCCCCUGGGCAGUGCAGAGCAGUUCCUCCUCACCCUGUCCUCCAUCAGCGAGCUCUCUGCACGACUUCACCUCUGGGCAUUCAAAAUGGAUUAUGAAACUACAGAAAAGGAAGUAGCAGAACCACUCCUGGACCUGAAGGAAGGAAUAGACCAGUUGGAGAACAAUAAAACCUUGGGCUUUAUCCUGUCUACUCUCUUAGCCAUUGGGAACUUUCUAAAUGGAACUAAUGCCAAAGCGUUUGAGUUAAGCUACCUCGAGAAGGUUCCAGAAGUCAAAGACACAGUGCACAAGCAGUCGCUUCUCCACCAUGUGUGCACCAUGGUGGUAGAAAACUUCCCAGACAGCUCCGAUCUGUACUCGGAGAUCGGGGCCAUCACCAGGUCAGCCAAGGUUGACUUUGAUCAACUUCAGGAUAAUUUAUGUCAGAUGGAGAGAAGAUGCAAAGCUUCAUGGGAUCACCUCAAGGCAAUUGCAAAACAUGAAAUGAAACCAGUUUUAAAACAACGGAUGUCAGAGUUCCUGAAAGACUGUGCAGAGCGAAUUAUAAUUUUAAAGAUUGUCCAUAGAAGGAUAAUCAACAGAUUCCACUCCUUUUUACUCUUUAUGGGCCAUCCACCUUAUGCAAUUCGGGAAGUGAACAUAAACAAAUUCUGCAGGAUUAUUAGUGAAUUUGCACUAGAGUAUCGCACAACCAGGGAAAGGGUUUUGCAGCAGAAACAGAAACGGGCCAACCACAGAGAGAGAAAUAAGACCAGAGGGAAGAUGAUCACCGAUUCUGGCAAGUUCUCCGGCAGUUCUCCGGCGCCCCCAAGCCAGCCGCAGGGUCUGAGCUAUGCGGAGGACGCGGCUGAGCACGAGAACAUGAAGGCUGUGCUGAAAACCUCGUCCCCCUCCGUGGAGGACGCCACCCCCGCGCUGGGCGUCCGCACACGCAGCCGAGCAAGCCGAGGAUCCACUAGUUCCUGGACUAUGGGAACUGAUGACUCGCCCAAUGUCACAGAUGAUGCAGCUGAUGAGAUCAUGGACCGCAUCGUCAAGUCAGCCACCCAAGUGCCCAGUCAGCGAGUGGUGCCGAGGGAGAGGAAACGAUCCCGGGCCAACCGGAAAUCUUGAACCAAAAAGAGUCUUCAGGAGUACUGGAUGCUAAUGUAGCCACAGGUAUAGUAGGAGGGCAUGGGCUGGGCUCUGCAAGGCCAAGGAAGCCACAGCCAGACCAGUGAUGGCAGAAAGCGCCUAAUGCCAUGAGUAUUUCUGAGUGCUGUCUCAGCCUCAGUGAACUUCAUCUUGGGUUAGAUGGAACUAGGAGACUUCAACCUUGUCACCACAGACUGUCACUGUCCUGAAAACCCCGCCUUUUCCUGCAUCUCAGAUGACAGUGAUUUAAGUGAGGGGCCCCAAACCUGGACAUCUGAUUACCCAGGGAAGGUUCAAAUGCAGUGCCUGAGCCUCUCCCCAAGACUCUUGCUCAGUGUGUCUGGGGUGAGUCCAAGAAAUUGAAUUUCAGUCAACUAGAUUUGGGAAUGUCUGCUUUUUGUUGUUGUUCUGGGUUUUAUCGCUUCAACGUUUUAUUCUGAAAAAAUAUAAGACUUACAGAAAAGUUGCAAAAAUAGUAGGACAAUUUAGCAAAACCAGGAAAUUCAAACUGGUACAGUACUAUUAACCGAACUGUAGGCUUUAUUCAGAUUUCACCAGUUUUGCCACGAAGGUCCUAUUUUUGCUCUACGAUCCUACCCAGGAUUCCAGAUUGCAUUUAGCCCUCAUGUCUGCUUAGUCUCCUCUAAUCUGUGAGGACACUUUGUGACCUUGGUAUUUUUGAAAAUUACCGGCCAGUUAUUUUGUAGAACAUCCUUCCAUUUGGGAAGGCUGUGCAUAUAAUGGACAGGAUUUUAUGUGGAAAAAAAGGAAGUCCUAGGGAGCACAUCUGGCCCUGCCGUUUUACGUCCACUCAGAACAAGGAGGGCGUGAAUGGACGGUGUUGAACAGUGGCCAAGCCCGGGACCUCCCAGCCACAAGACAUGGACAUUUAAGGCAUCUUGAAGUUCUGAUGUUAGUCAACUAGACUCCUAGACACAUUGCUCCCAGUACACCUGGUAGAAAAUCUUUGGGAUCUUUGGGAUUAAAAAACCAAAAAACGAUUUUCAAAUUACACUUGAUAAUUAUGUGCAAAAAAACCCCGAAAUAACAUCUCUCAGUGCUGCAAAGGUGAAAGCGCACAGAUGGAUUUCUGUCACCUGAAAGUAAAGUUGGGUCGAUUUCCUGUUGAUGUGAAAGAUGGUCAGGAACUGUCCUGCCAAGCAUCGGCAGGGCACAGCUGUUUCCAGUGUGGACUGUGAUCCAAAGUCGGCUCAAACCCUUCUCUACCACUAAGUGUGAGCCCUGGGCCAGUGACCAGGUUCUCUGGUCCGGGUUUGCUCACUUAUUGAAGAUAUAACAAGAGUUCCCAUCUCACAGUGUUUCCAUAAAGAUUAAGUGAAACAACCCAUGUAAACACUCAGUAAAUGGUGGCUGCCAUUGCCAUUGUUCUCGGAUGCGACUCAUCUUAGUAGAGUCACCUGUGAGCCCUUUGUGGGAAUUUUUAAUGUUUUCAUUUCUAGGGAGGAAGAAAAAGAACUUGGGUGUUUUUCCUGAGUCCCCAGACAGUCCUGUGCUGCAUGCUGGCAGCAGAGGCACCCCACAUCAGAUUCUUCCACCAUCACUUUGACACCGUGAGAACUGUCACCAGGGCCUGGGGUGCAGUGUGGCUGCUGGUGCCUUCAGAGUGACCCAUGCCAUCUAUGGCAGAGUUGCAAGGCAGACAGGGAUAAACAUUUCCAGUCUGUUCUCUGUUAUGAGCUUUGAGGGGAGGCCGUCCCGUGGGAAAGGCUGGAGAGCAGCUUUGAUUCAGCUGGAGCAUUUGAGUGGGAAGUGGAAAUGAGGAGUCGGGAGAGGCCCAGGUGUCAUCCGCAGCCAGCCGACCUUGCCACAGUGCUGGAGAAGCCUCUCUACUGGGUGGCAGAGUUGUUUCUGCUGUGGAAGUUUGCUGUGUACCAUUUCAUACCCUGCCAGCACCUGUUUGCUGGCCCCCUUGUUUUGUUCUCUUAUGUCCCCAGCCUUUUUUUUUUUUUUGCUUUCUGGAAACUUUCUGAGAGCCAGCUCCCUGGCUGGACCCCAUCUGCUGCCCUGAGUGUUUCUCCCCACACUGUGUCCCCAUCAGGCCCCUGCCUUUCUCCCCAGAGGCUCCCAUCGCAGAGGCUCAGGGUGUACAUGUACAUGAUGUUUGAUGAAUGGCAAAGAAACUGACCAGCAGACAGAUGGUUGACCAAACACCCAAAGGGGCUCUUGUCGCGUGUGACUUGAAUUGGGUGUAAGACUGAUUUUAGCUGAUUACUUUCAUUUCACGUGGUCUUUCAAGUGGUGAGGUGAAUUAACUUUGGCUAACAAAGGGAAGGUUUCAGAUUCUCAGGUAUUUUUCAUUACACCAAGGGGAUAACAUAUAUCUAAGAGAAUUUUUUUCAAAUUGCCAUGGAGGUCCACAGAAAGUAGAAUUUCAUAAAUGGGGAAGACUUUUCCAUGAAUACUCGCUUUUCAGGGAUACAUCUGGCAAGCUAAGGGAAUGAAGCCUAUGUUGGCUUUUCCCUCACAGCAGAGGACACAUGAGCCCAGACCAGAGGGUGAAGCAGCAUCCCAAGGGGUCUGGAAUAUCCAAACCAUGAGUAGACCCACGAGGGAGAGGGCACAGGCUCUGUGCUGUCAGGUAGCAAGACCCAUAAAGGUACCUUUAGUUCUGUUCUCUGAGCCUGUCCCAGAUAGGCUGGCUCAAUGUCCGAAGCUAUUAAAAGAUUGUUACAUGAGCUGUAAGGUGACCGGGCCCUUAUUCGAGUAUUAAUAUUUAUAUCAACUGAACUGAGCAGUUACAGGACUAAAGCAAAUGUGCAAACAGAAUUGUUAAGCAUCUUUAAAUACCUUCAUGGGUAAAAUAUCUGUGGGGUCUUCUGUAGUCAUUCAGCCACAAUAUAUACCUAAAUGGACAAAGAUUCAUAGACUGAUGUCCACACCACCUUCUGUGGCUGGUGAAAUUUUAAGAUGCCCAGCUAGUGCAGCAUGAACUACUUCUUCUUCUUUUUCUUUUUUUUUUUUUUUUUUUUUUGAGAUGGGGCCUCGCUCUGUCACCCAGGCUGGAGUGCAGUGGCACCAUCUCGGCUCACCGCAACCUCCGCCUCCCAGGUUCAAGCAAUUCUCUGCAUCAGCUUCCCGAGUAGCUGGGACUACAGAUGUGUGCCACCAUGUCUGGCUAAUUUUUGUAUUUUUAGUAGAGAUGGAGUUUCACCAUGUUGGUCUCAAGCUGCUGACCUCAAGUGAUCCACCUGCCUCAGCCUCCCAAAGUGCUGGGAUUACAGGUGUGAGCCACUGUGCCCGGCCAGCAUGGACUUUUUAAGGAAGUAUUUUGUAUCUUGGUUAAGAAGUUGCAGCAAGAGGUCUUUCUUGUCAAGAGAGAUAUUUUAUCUUAUUUACUGUUGUUAAAAUUAUCUUUCUUUAACAAACACUCUAAGGAGUCUUUAAAGAACAUAAAAGGUUAUUACAAACUAGUAUUUUUAUUGCUGCCCCAUAGAACAAAUUCUGUUGCUCAGUUGAAUGUAAUCUGUCUCCAGCUGAGACUUAGGAGCCAAACAUUUUGUCUUGUUGAGCCAAACAUUCAGUCUGGAGGCCAAGGGAUCAGGGGUGGGGGAAAGAGGAGCUAGUGCAAGAACAGCUACAGAUAGAUUGCUUCAGGGCCCAAAGGUAGGCUUGGAAAUACAGUAGUUGCAGUAACACGAUUUGAGAGAACCCCUCACCACAUAUCCCAUGUCUCUCUAAAAACCCAUACUUGAUGUCUGUGUUUUGAUUCUUUGAGUUAAAUGCUGAGCACACAAUGGGUUCUCAAUAAAUCAUUUGUUGGUUGACCAAUUGAUGGAUAUUAUGUUGACCCCUGUUCCAAGUGCUGAUUCCUGGAAGAGAAGGAGCCCUUUAUUUUCAUAAUAGGUAUUAGUCCCCAUUGAUUCUGCCAUGGACAUAGGUCUUUCAGAUCUUUUGUCCACAGGCUGAGUGAGCUUAUAUUUAGGGGAUGAUGGGAAGGCAUAGACCAUGGGGUGUGGCCUGCAGAUGCAUGAGGUGGGCCCUGGCCUCUGGGGAGUAGAUGAGGGGAGUUGGCAAAGGAACUGGGGAGACAUUAAGGUGAGCUUACUUUCUCUGAACUUUGAUCAACAGCCUGCCCUGGUCAUCUCAGGAACUCUGGCUGAUUUAGGGAUUUAGGGUGAAGGCAGAUCCAUAACGUUUCUCUUCUGAAAAUGAAUACCCCAAACUCUGUGCGAACUUUAAAGAAAUACACAGUGGGUCAAAUACAAUUUGUAAAUUAAGGAAAAUGUAAUUAGCCACCCUUUCAAAUGAAGACUUGUCUUGGGUGAGGCAGCUACCUCCUCAUUCACCCUUAUCCAGCCUUUAUUUUGAUGUUGAAAUUGAAAUACUAAACAAUGGGAAUACCAUCAUGCCAAGCUAAACACAAGCCAAUUCUAAGUCAGUUAAAUAUGAGCAUCCCUCCAGUUGCCAACUGCAACCCCCCAGUGAGAGUGGUCAUUGGCCAUUCUUGAGUCUUGUGUGUUCCAUAGAAAACAGCCACCAAUUCCAGCCAGAAUAAGUUUGGCAGUUUGCUCCUUAGCCUCCAUUCCUCGAGGAGCCACUGGUUAUUUUAAUUAUUGUCUCUAGAGGCCUUUUAGUGAGUUGAGGCUAAGACCCACAGUACUCAUGGAGAGAUUUGUCCUCACUGCUGCCCCUUGCCCUGGCUUCAUGCACUUGCUCUGUGGGUCUUGAGCAUGUCCCCAGCUAUUGUUGGUCGUCUGUUGGAUUUGUGAGGUUGUUGGGUCUUGUGGAACCCCUCGCUGUGCACUGGUUGCCUCACCUCAUUUGUAUUAGUGGAGCUUGCAUUUUCCCCUGCUCUGGAAUCACCUUCCCAGCUCUGAUACACUCCUCAUACUGGGUAGAUGCUGAGGUCUCUCCUGCCCUCUGCACUUCUGCAGUUCACCCCCUUCUCAGAAGCCUCGUGAGGGUGAGCCUCUCCUCCUUUCUCUCCUCUUUAUAAGUGCCCGCAUCACUCCUCUCGGCCCUCCAAAUCAGCACCUGUGGCAUUGUUAGGCCAGCCUGUGUAGCCCCAAACUUUUGUCCUGGCAGACAGACUGCAGGGCACUUCAGCAAGAGCAGGAAGGUACAGAGUGUGAACCCUCUGGCUUCUCUGGAAGUCCCUGGGGAGAAGGGGGGACUGGAGUCUUGACUGCCCUGUGCCUUGCUGCUCAUACUUCCUUUUCUUCUCAUCCCUUUGGGUGUGACCUGCACCACCACUGCAGUGCGAAGAACCCUGAAGAGCGGCCUGACCCCAGAAGAAGCCAGAGCCCUGGGCUUGGUUGGCACCUCGGAGUUGCAGCUGUGACACUCAUAGGUUACUCCCAGGAGUGUGCUGAGCAGAAGGCAAGCUCUUGCUGGAUGAAACCCCUCCAGGUGGGGUUGGGGAGACUUGAUAUUCACAUCCAACAGUUUGAAAAGGGAGAGCUCAAUUCCCAGCGUCACCCCAUGGCUUGUGUUGCCUGCUACGCAUUGACUUGGAUCUCCAGGAGUCCCCUGCACAUACCUUCUCCAUCGUGUCAGCUGUGUUUCUCUUGAUUCCGUGACACCCGGUUUAUUAGUUCAAAAGUGUGACACCUUUUCUGGGCAAGGAACAGCCCCUUUAAGGAGCAAAUCACUUCUGUCACAGUUAUUAUGGUAAUAUGAGGCAAUCUGAUUAGCUUCACAGACUGAGUCUCCACAACACCAAAAUAUCCAGAUGUAAACCCCAAACUUGUACACAAAAGAAAGCACAGAUUGUUUACCUGUUGUGGAUUUUAGAUGUAACAAAUGUUUAUACAAAUACAUACAUGUACACCAUGUUUCAAAUACUAAAUAAAUAGAGUUUAAUGCCA